ACACACACACACAUUUGCUCACACAAACCACACAAACUUUAAGCCUUGUGAAGCUGCCCAGGUGGUGUGUAGGAAAUUUUGGUAGAGAAAGAAAUAGUUUGAAAGUUGGUUUCUGACAAGAGGAAAGAAAAGGCUGCAACACUAAAGGAAGACUCAAAGUGUUAAAAGGACGCUCAAAAUGUAGUAUUGUGGCAGGUCGGGGUAAGUUAUAUUUUCUUCUGUUUUCUCUUUGGUUUUGGAACGCAGUGAAAAUGCACUGUGGGGAGUUUUUCUGUUGUUUUUAAGAAAUGAAAUAAUACUCCAAGCUCCCUCCUAGGAUGACUUCCUCCUGCGACUUUGCUCUGUUUUUGUGGGUGUUCUACAGAGAGGCGCUUUCUCCUAGAGCCCUGUCAUCAUAGACCCAGAGGCCCUCAAAUUCUGAGUGGCCAGGGUUUGGAGAGCCGCUUUCGGGUCGCAGAGGCAACAAGUCGUGGACUCUCUAGCCCCAGGCAAGCGCCGCACCGCGCCGCAGCUGAGCCUGUGGCUCGCCUGACUCAGGAAUGAAUUUUGCACGUGUAAACUACUUGCCUGUGGAUGCGCACAGCUGCGACUCUGGGGUUUAUCAAGGGAAAAAAACUAUUCCUUUAAAUGGACGAUUUGCAAAAACUCAGCCAUUGGUUCUUGCCAAAUGACUAUUGAUGCAGAGUAAACCCUACCGGUUGGUGCGUGCGCACGUUUGUUUAACCCUAAAAAUAUUCCACUUCCGAGUUGCUCAAGUUGACAUCCACUUGAAAUCAUUUGUAUUUUUUUUUAGGGGCUGGAAAAAUAACUGGCAUUAUCUGUGGGAGACGGUGUAGAUAUAUUGGUGGGGGAGGCAUAUUUCACUGGAAAGUGAUGCCCUGUAUUCGCUGAACGUAGGGAAGUGUCCCAAAGAAACGCGGCUCCCAGUGCGCGCGCAUACCACAUUUCCACAAACGUGUGUUACAAAUGCACUUUCCUGCCACUAACCUGCAGCUUUGAGAUUCGAUUCUGAGGUUUAAAUAAUAUUGUUUUUCUGCAUGGCAUGGAUAUUCAGACGCCAGCAAUGAGCAAUCCUUCAUUUGAGUACCUGCAAGCGUCUGCAGCAAGCUAGAUUUUAUUUAUUAUUAUUAGCUUUCUGCUACCAGAAACGUGGAAUAAACAUGUGCUGCCCCAGAAAUUGGGCGGAGCUGAUCCAGAUGUUGGCAAACACGUCUUUACCAGUUGUAUUUCUGAGGAAGCCCAGAGAAAUGGAUCAGAGAGCCGAAGAGAAAUUGACAAGGGAGCUGAUCAGAGGCGAUUUUGUUCAUUAGCAGGAGCGACUCCUGCUUUGGGUCUGGCGGGGGCGAGCAUAUAAAAUGCAACUUUUGCCCCAUUGGUUCGCUAGGUGAAUUAGCACAUACUGGGACUGAACAGUCCUUGACCUUUGCCUUUAUGUUUGCGCAAAUGUUUGCCUAAAACACAAUCGGUCUUGACAAGAGAGCAUGCUACCGUGUGACACUGCCUAUUCACCAGAUAGAUGUUCCCUGCCACACACGACCCAGAGCAGCCUUUUAAAUAGCUUAGGUAUUUGCACAAACUGUAUAAAUUAAUGUCGGAUGAUUGCUAGUUGCUGGUUAAAUAGGAGAGAGAUGAUUUAGAUGAGGAAUACAUGUAUCUCUCUGGCAUUUUUUUUCUUGCCAAAAAAGUCGGUAAGAUAACUGAUAGCGAAGGAAAGUUUAUGUUUGUGGGAGUCAAAAGGUUCUUGUUUGAUCAAAGGGCACAUGAAUGUAGUUUUCUUACAAAUGGCUUUUCCACAAAGAUGGGGAGUGGAUGAAGGAAGAGGAGAGAUGGAGAGUGGAGAAAGCUGUGAGAAACUAAUAAUUAGGAUAACUGGUAAUGGGGAGGUUUAGAAUAUGAUUCUGGAGGAUUUAUUGUUCCUAAAGGAGCCAUGGCCAGCCAGCAGCCUCUCAGUGCUCUGGAAACCCCAUGAAACUUGGGGGGAAGUUAUCCCGAUUACUGAGCUUUAUGGCUUUGAACUCUUCCUUCAGUAAAACCAAAUACUUUAGCAGGAGGAGAAAAGCACCUUUUAGAAUCUAAAAUUGGUUUAAGUCUUUUAAACCUCUCACUAUAGAUGUGAAAUUAUUUAGAUAACUGGGCUGCCUUUUCCCGAACUUUGACAUAGGAGCAAAAUGAACUUUCCUUAACUGUGGUUUCUAGCUGAGAUCAGAAUUUUCCACAUUCCUUUCAUUAUCUGCAACAUGGUAAAACCUCACCAAUUUCCAUGGCUCAAUUCUGUUGGCAGGACUACCAAGACAGGGAGAGCAAAUUAAGAAAAAUGAGGAUAUUUUCAAUAUUCUUUCAGGGAGGUUCAUUCCCUUGAAAGAGAGGAGUAUUUACUUCUUUCAGUCCAAGGGAUGCAGUAGACGAGGGUAGCACCAACUCAUGCCACAGUCUGGGAAUGCAGAUUUGAAUGUCUGAAAGCCACUGUGAUUUCUCCAAACAUUUGCAAGGUAUUUUUCAGAUUUCCAUGAACUGUAUUCAGGUGGAGAAGAGGGAGGGUUCACCAGUUCUCCCUUGGAAAUCCUUUCUCUUGAUCCCUGGGCAAAAUUUGCCUUCUCUCUGUUGGGCUAUGGAGACUUUCAGGGUAGGAGAAAGUUUGUUUAAAAGCCAUGUUCCACAUUGACUUUAGGUACAGCACAAAAGUAGCAGAAAGGUAAAAACAUCAAUCUUAGAAUGAAAAAAAUAAUACGUUUAUGAACAAGCACCUAGAAUAAAAUUAAGGGGACUCUCUCCAUUUUUCAAUAAUCUCCAUAAUAAUUUCUUAACUAACAGAAAUAAUUUGUUAAGUUAUUCUUAUUUCUUACUUACUUAACAAUGUAAUAAGUAUGAACUACUUCAAAACACUUUUUUAAGGUAGAUGCAAAACGUCUACCUUAAAUGUCUGUGCAUUUUGGCUUUAGGUUCAGCAAUAUGGGCAACUAAAUAUACAUAAAAAUCAUAUUUCAAUUCUCAGAGGGUAUUUGUCCGUUUUAUUAAGUGUAUGCACAACUGCUUUUUCAAAGUUGUUUUAUUUUAAAAUAAAAUGAUUCUAAAUGUUCUCUUCUCUUUGCUAUGUACCACAUCCUACAAUCUUCAGAAAAUUUAGGAAUUAAAGACAUAGAAAGGCAAAUAUUAGGGUUCUAUUCUCUGGGAUAUCCUACAGUGACAUAGUGUAGGCAAGGCAGCAAUAUGUUUCUAGCCUUUUCUUCCCUGUACCUGGGGUUGUGAUGGGUUAAGUUUAUUCAGGGUUAUGAGUAAAUUGGGACCUAGAAUCUACAAUCCAUGAUGAUGAAUACAAGGGACUUAGAUUUAAAUCUAGUUGUUACAAAAAUCAGCUUAGGAAUUCAAUAAAUUUCCAAAUUUGCACAAUUUGAAACAGAAACAUUUUUAAAAAUCAUUAGAAAAAAAUCUGCAUAUUAUAUAAAACGUAUCUCACAUAUAUUCUAUCCAUCAAAAAUUCAAGUACUUACUCCAUUCAUUUAAUUAUAGUAACUACAAUUGAAGAUAAAAGUUGGUUAGUUCCAUUUUUUGCUGACAGACAUCUAUUAAUAGAGUUUGUGCAUAUUUUUGGCCAGAGCUAAAAAUACCAUUAAAUGUUUAUAUUGUGAAAUCUGUCAAUGGUUUUACCUAGAAGUGUUCAAGAGAACAUAUAGUGACUUAUUGAUAUCAAUAAAGACACAGCACAAUUGCCAGAAGUGUUCUUAUUCAAACAAAUAACACAAAUUAAAUAAGGAAGAAAGGAGGAAAAAAUAUUUUUAUACUUUAUAAAAUAUAAGUAUAUUCAUAAUUGAAAAAUUAAGGUAAUUGAUUUAUUCUUAUAAGAGUUGAGUAUGUGACAGUUGUCUAUUGAAAAAUUGUUUGCAUAUAAAAUUAAUAUUUCUUAAAGGUAAAAUGAUUGCACUUACAAGACACCAUAACUGUAAAAUUUGUUAGAUGACUCUAGUACACAUUAACUUCUAUAUAAAUAAUAUUCUUACUGACUGGAUUAUAAAAUGACACCUACUAUAGUCUGUGAAGUUUUUACAUUUUUACUAUGCAUUGAAAUUAAAGUGAAGAAGUAAAGUCAGAUUAUAGGACUUGGAACUAUCCGAGAGAGCCAAGAGGAAGUACCCUGUUUGCAUUGUAUUUCUUCCAAGGUAGUUAUUUCCCCCUAAUAUAUGUAGAUGAGGCUUGUAUUGUUCUAAAAAUCCUCAACAAUUAUUUGCUAUUAAUUUAACUCCACUUUGUAAGUAAAAAUUUAGAGAUGCUUUGGAGUCAUGUGUAUUUAACUAGCAAGUACUGAACUUAAUUGGAAUAGCCCAGAGAUUCCACUUCCAGGUCCUUUGUCUGUGCCUAUGAGUAGGCAGGCCAUGCUAGAGUCGGGGUUCAGAGAACAGUCAUUCUCUGGUGGCUUUCUUGGUACAGAGAAAUACAGUUCUCAUCCCCCGUUUUGAUUCACAACUUCUGACCAAUAAAUUGUGCUCUGAUUUCCCAUGCCUAUUGCAUCUACCACCACCCUGCCCUAAUCACCUGCUCUUGACAAAGAGAGUGCAGAAGCUGAGGCAGUAUAGUUCAGGGACUGGAUUCCAGAGGGGCAUUUGGAAGAAGCCACACCAAGCUUUGGAAAGCAAGUGAGAUUUGUGAUCUUGAUGCUUAGAAAUCUUUCCUAUGGGCAGUCUUGGAAAAUCUGGGAUUUCGAGAAGUCUGGGCCCCCAUUUUAAUCUUCUUUGGUGUAAAAACUGUGAAUUCAGAGUUAAAGAAGGGGGAAGGAGCAUUGCAGCCUUUAGAGAGGGGUUCAGGGCCUGAAGACCUGAAAAGUUCCCACACUUCAUUCGCACCUGACAUUUCAGGAGCCCCUUAAUUUAGUCACAGAAGUUGAUGCCCACAGGGAGCGAGAAUUUGGCAGGUACCAGGUGCUUCAGCAGGACUCGGGCUCAUUCUCUGAUUUAGCUAAAGCUGUCUGGUGAGGGAACAAGGGGUCAUAAGUAUGCUGUUUGUUUGUUUGUUUGUUUGUUUUGUUUUUGUUUUUCAUUUGUUUUGUUUUGUUUUUAGCUCCUGACCCUCAUUCAUAUGUCAGAUCCCCAUUUCCCUUACCCUUCACUCCCUUUGUCAGUAGCUUGGAAGACUGUGGAGCCCUCUUGCUUUCUCCCACUCCACCCUCCUCUCACCUUCCCCCACCCUCUUUUACUGUCUCACACCACCUCACCUUUCCAUACUCCGUCAACCCUUCUUAAACCUCACCUUCUCACACUCAUAGCCCCUCAUAUUCUCUUCUACCCAUCUCCCCCUCUAAACCCCUACUACUCCUCAUCCUCCACUUCCACAGAAUCCCACAAAUCCCUCACAUCUACUUCAUCCUCCUCACUUCCCUCAGACAAUUUGCCACCUCCAAUCUCUUCAUCUCCACAGCCUACACUCUCACACAUUCUCUCAAAGCCCCCAGACUCUUCUUGCCCACUCACAAUUAGAACCUCACUCACUCUUUCACAUCAGUCACCUCCCCAUGCCUUCAUAUCCCACAAGGUGUCUCCAGGCAUCCCUUCCCCCCAACUCUUACACCCACCAUAUUCACAUCCUCUAUACCUUCCACACAUACUUCACCUUCAGACUCCUACUCCCAGUCAGGCACACAAGUCAUCUCCCCCUGCCUUUUCCUGGGUGGUAUCUGAACUCCUCAGUCUGUGUUGGAGAACCUUGCCUCAAGUGUCUUCCCCUCUGACUCUUCCUUCCAUAACUUUCUUCCCUACCAGAGUGUCAGCAUAUCCCUCUCUGGAGUUCUCUUUGGAGAAGAGCACAUGGCUAUCUCCCUUUCACUUUUUUCACUCACCAGGGCUCGUAGUCACAGCAAAGUGGGACUGGGAACCUAAACAGUUGUCCCCUAGAUCCAGUGCUGGGCUACGUGUGGAUGGGAAGCCAGGGCCGCUCAUUGGCUGCUCUGUUCUCAGCCCUCAGCUUCAGAGGGCUUGUCCUUGUCUUUCCUCCCAGAUUUGUUUUCAGUCUUCAGGGAUACAAACUCCUACAUUCAACAUUUCCAUUAGCAGGGUGAGUGGGUAGGAAAGAUUCUUUAAACUGGAGAUUCUCCAAUUUGAUCAAGGUUUAGAAUCACCCAAAGUUUGUUUAAAAACAAACAAAAUAAAACAUAACUAGAAAUUGCUUGGCCCCAUUUUAACAGUUUAUGUGAAUUUACAUUUCUAAUAAGUUCCCAGGUGAUGCUGGGACCACAUUUUGAGGCAAUUUGAGCAAUGUUCAGCAGGAGGAAGUGACUCUAUUUGUACAGUGAGAAGACACAGGGAGAUCCAUAGAACUCAGAGGUUCAAGAGGAGAAUGACACUCAGUGGAUAGAUGGGAACAGUUUCCUAAAAAUGUCCUAAAUGAGAAGGUACUUUGACAGUAGGUUUUAUUCUACAAGGUUAGGGCUUUUUCUAUGAGAGGAAGGGAGGAAGAAAGAAGACUGUGCCUAGGACAUCUCCUUUCCUAAGCUCUCGCUGACCAUUUAAAAUGAAGCUAAGAUGUUUAGAAUUUGUAGGGGACUGGGUCUUGAGUCACUGAAAGUGCUAGUCACUCUGUUUAGGUUUAUUGUUUUUGAGCCUCGGGAUCUGUGUGUGUGUGUGUGUGUGUGUGUGUGUGUGUGUGUGUGUAGGCUUGCUCUCUGCCUUUGCAUUUAAGUUUCAUUCAAAAUGGAUGGAACCACUCAGGCCCUACAGAAUCACCUUUUCUAGCCUAGGUAGUGGUUACUAUGGUUACUUCCUGUUUCCUUUCCAUGUGCCUAUGACCAGACCUCACAGAUAUCUCCCUUCAAUUCUCCCUGAGGGCUAAAAGGUGGCCCAGAAACUUUUGGCCAGUUAACAUUCUGCCUUAUCAAUUGUCUAGGGAGUAGUUUUCUAAAUUUAUUUGGAACUGCAAAGGUAAAUAAAUGAAGGAAAAAAUACAUAAGAGAGAAAAGGUCAAGUUCUUCAAACUGGAACUUUCUUGUGUGUGUGCGUGUGGAUAUGUCUAUGGUACAUUUAACCAGUAAGAGAACACAUACCAUAAGCAGUCAUGUUGCUAGACAAAAGUUUUCUUUGAUUUUGUAUUUGAAUUUACUUAACAACAUAAAUUUUAAAUACUAAUCCUGGUCACUUGGGCCAAGAACAUUUAUAUAUUUUUCUCCCAGCUGAUUUUAUCAACAGUUUUCAAUCUCAUUUUCUCAAGACUUUUAGGCCAAGGCAGAAUUUUCUAGCCUUCCUUUGGAGAUCAGGAUCCAGAGAUUAGAGUUCUGGGAUCUUGGCAAGGGUUUGUACUACUUUUUCCAUGAUGUUUGCAAAUCCCUAGCAACAAUUCUGCAUUCUAAUUUUUUUCCUCCUUUCUUUGUACAUCACAAAUAAUUACACUGUUCAAACAUGGCUUAGAAAAAAACACAGUUACAUUAACAUGUCUCUUCUACAAUUUUGUUUUAGAAAUGACUAGAAUUUUCUGGUAAUUCAUAGUUUUUCUCCUGGUUUAAAAACAAAAAUAUUUAAAUUUUAUCUUGCCAAAUGUCUAUCAUUUGUUAGCACAUUUUGCUUGCUGUCCUUCAGCCUCUGAAGUUUAUGGACAUUAUUAAAAUGUUUGGGGGAUCAUCAGCACACCAGUUCCUUGAGAAAAUGUUGGGAUAGGCUUUACACUAUACAAUCCAGUUGUUCAGAAUUGAAAGGUUUUCAAGUUGAGUUUGCUUUUCUUUCUCUUAC